GUAGUUCUGCGCGUUCACGUCCCCGAUCGGGCCGUGUCCGCCGCGGCCCUGCGAGGUCCGAGGGACUCAUUCUGAUGAAGGAAAGAGCGUCCCUGUGCAGCUGCGUGUCCUUCAGUUCUUUGGCUCUGAUUCCGUGUCUGGCUUCAUCUAAGUGGCCUGGUCCAUGGGCAGUGAAGAAAUGUAAAGUGCAAUAGCCCUCUGGAACAAGACAAUUCAUGUGAGAUAAGAAAGAAGAGCCCACAAGACCAAGGAUGUAUUCUCAGUUUACAGACCACUGACCAGAGGCCACUCCAGGGUGUCAGGACUAAGAGAAGUCACAAAACAGCAGAUUUCCCAAGAGCAGCGGAAAAUGAUCCAGUCACAGAUAUCAUUUGAGGAUGUGGCUGUGGAUUUCACGCUGGAGGAAUGGCAGCUACUUAAUCCUACUCAGAAGAACUUGUACAGAGAUGUGAUGUUGGAGAACUAUAGCAAUCUGGUUUUCUUGGAAGUCUGGCUAGAUAAUCCCAAAAUGUGGCUCCGAGAUAAUCAAGACAACCUUAAAAGUAUGGAGAGAGGCCAUAAAUAUGAUGUUUUUGGAAAAAUAUUUAAUUCAAGCAUAAACAUUGUUCAUGUAGGACUGCGAUCCCAUAAAUGUGGCACAGGAGAAAAAAGUUUGAAAUGUCCUUUUGAUUUGCUUAUUCCAAAAAAUAAUUGUGAAAGAAAGAAAAUUGAUGAACUCAAUAAGAAAUUAUUGUUCUGUAUCAAACCUGGCAGAACCCAUGGUGGGAUAAAAUACUGUGAUUGCAGUACAUGUAGAAAAUCCAGCAACGAAGAGCCAUGGCUCACUGCUAAUCACAUAACACACACAGGAGUCUAUUUAUGCAUGGAAUGUGGCAGAUUUUUUAACAAGAAGUCACAACUUGUUAUACACCAGAGAACUCAUACAGGAGAGAAGCCCUAUCAAUGCAGUGAGUGUGGAAAAGCCUUUUCACAGAAGUCACUGCUCACGGUUCAUCAAAGAACUCACUCAGGAGAAAAACCGCAUGGGUGCAGCGAAUGUCAGAAAGCUUUUAGUAGGAAGUCACUCCUCAUUUUACAUCAGAGAAUUCAUACUGGAGAGAAGCCGUAUGGAUGCAGUGAAUGUGGAAAAGCCUUCAGUAGGAAGUCGCAGCUUAAAAGACAUCAGAUAACGCACACAAUAGAGAAACCCUACAGUUGCAGUGAGUGUGGGAAAGCAUUCUCCCAGAAAUUAAAACUCAUCACACAUCAGAGAGCGCACACAGGAGAGAAACCCUAUCCAUGUAGUCACUGUGGAAAAGCCUUCUUUUGGAAGUCGCAGCUGAUUACUCAUCAGAGGACCCACACAGGGAAGAAACCUUACGGAUGUGGUGAGUGUCAAAAAGCCUUCAGCAGGAACUCACUUCUCAUUAGGCAUCAGAGGAUUCAUACAGGAGAGAAGCCCUACGAAUGCAACGAAUGUGGUGAAGCCUUCAUCAGAAAACCACAGCUGAUUAAACAUCAGAUAACUCACACAGGAGAGAAGAACUAUCGAUGCAGUGAUUGUGAGGAGGCCUUCUUUAAGAAGUCAGAGUUAAUAAGACAUCAAAAAAUUCACUUAGGAGAGAAACCAUAUGGAUGCAUUCAAUGUGGGAAAACCUUCUUUGGGAAGUCCCAGCUCCUAACGCAUCACAGAACACACACUGGGGAGAAGCCUUAUGAAUGCAGUGAGUGUGGGAAGGCCUUCACCCAGAAGUCAAGCCUGAUAUCACAUCAGAGAACACAUACAGGUGAGAAACCCUAUGAAUGCAGUGAAUGCAGGAAAACCUUCAGUGAGAAGUCAAGUCUCAUUCAUCAUCAGAGAACCCAUACUGGAGAAAAGCCCUUUGAAUGUAGUGAAUGUAGGAAAGCUUUUGCCUGGAAGCCACAGCUUCUUAGGCAUCAGAGAAUUCAUACAGGGGAGAAACCCUAUGAAUGCAGUGAAUGUGGGAAAGCAUUUGUUCAGAAAGUGCAGCUCAUUAAGCAUCAAAGAAAUCACACAGGAGAGAAAACCUAUGGAUGCAGCGAUUGUGCAAAAGCUUUCUUUGAGAAGGCACAGCUGAUUAUACAUCAGAGAAUUCAUACAGGAGAGAGACCAUAUAAAUGUGGUGAAUGUGGGAAAUCUUUCACAAGAAAGUCACACCUUAUGAGGCAUCAGAGGAUUCAUACAGGAGAUAAAUACUAUGGAUGCAAUGAGUGUGGGACCACCUUCAACAGGAAGUCGCAGCUUAUGAUACAUCAGAGAAAUCAUAUAAUAUAAAAAUCAUGACUUUGGCGAAUGCAGAAAGGUUGCUAUCAAGUGUCAUACUUUCUGACACUUUUGAGGAUGCAUGUGGGAGAGAAACCCUAUUGAGGCAGUGACUGUUGAAAAAGCUUGAAUUGAGGAGUCAAGAGUCACUAAGCAGAAUUUAGAAAGAGAAGUUUUUAAAAAGCAAACAGUGUAAAAAAAGUCAUCUCCCAGAAGACACUACUCGUUACAUAUUGGAUGACUCAUUGAGGUGAAAACCUUAUUAGUGUUGUGAUAGUAGAGAAGCUUUUAGUCAAAAGUCAGUUUAUUAAAUGUUUAGAAUACCUAAACAGGAAGAAAAUUCUAUUGUUUUUUAUAACAAAGUGGAAGAUUUCAAGAAAGGACAACUCACUGUACACUUGAGAAUAAUACCUACAGAGGUUCAUACUGAAGAGUAGUCUCAAUAAUGUAAAGAAUUUGACAAGCAUGAUGCUAUUGAAAUAGUUCUGUAAGGAAGUGGUGUUCUUUAUACAUCAAUUAUUACAAAAAGCAGUGAAUUGUAAGUGUGAGGUGUGUUUACUUAGAUGUGAAGAGUUCUCCUUACUGCUGUGAUGGAAUAACAAGGGUCAGAUUUCCUCUCCUGCCUUAAACAACUGGAAGCUAUACAAUACGUAUAAUAGGUAAUGGUUUUUAGACAUAGGACAAGCACAGGUUUGUGAUCCUCAGGAGACUGCAGACAGAGUGAGGUGAGCACCAUGGUUUCUCAGCCUGCCCCCGCAUGGCAGUUCCUAGGUUGCAGUUCAGGGAAGGGAAACAAUAAAUCUCGCUGAAUUGAAGAGACAGGACUGGCAGUUGGGGAGGCCACAGCAGCUAGAAUUUCCAGGGGAAAGUACUGGAGAGAUGGGAUCCUUCUAGAUACAGGGCUCAAGAAGUCUGCUGGGAGUCCCCUGAGUCCUUUGACUUAGUACUGACUUGCACUGAGGCCAGGAAAAGAAGCACUGGAAAGCAGCAGGCUGAACAAUUCCUGGAACUCAUGCAGGGCUGGGAAUAGUUUAUGUUCUCAGCAGCCAGAGUGGAAACAGAGUGGAAACACAUGGAGCAUCAGGUAGAAUUCUCAGAAAGGUUUUGUUUUAGUAGUGCAGCUAAUUAACUCUAGAUUAAAAGCUACUCUGGACCUACAGUGUCCGGCAUCCAAAAAAACUAAUGUGUUAUGCAAAGAAGCAAUAAAAUAUGACUUAUAACCAGGAGAAAAAUCAGUAGAAACCCAGAAAAGACAGAGGUGAUGGAAUUAGUAGACAAGGAUAUUAAAAGAGCUAUUGUAAAUAUAAAGUAGAGGAAAACAUAAGAUUGAUGAAACCUGAGGUAUAAGAGAUAUUUUUACUGGCCAAAAUGGAACUUCUAGGGAUGAAAUCAACUUCUGAUUUUGUUAAAAUCCCGAGUGGAGAGAUUAGAUACAGAAAAAGAAGAAAAAAUCAAUGAACUUGAAGAGUAAGAAUAAAAACUACCAAAGUGAUAUACAGAGAGAAAAAAAGACUUAGAGAAGAGGAAGAGAAUAGGAAAACCAUUACAGUAGUGUAAUAUAUGUUUAACUGGAGUCCCAGAAGGAGAGGAGAAAAUGAAGAGGCAUGAAGAAGUAUUUGAAUAAAUAAUGGCUAAAGAUUUUCCAAAUCUGGUGAAAACAAUACCCCCACAUAUUCAAGAAGCUCAAAUGACCUGAAGUAGAAUAAACAUAAUUUACAUCACAGCAGUGCACCUCAGAGUCACAUUCAUGAAAAGCACUGAUAAACAGAAUACUUUUAAAACACCUUGAGAAAAAAAGAUAAUACAUACACAUGAACAAAGAAUGGCAGCAUAUUUCUGGUGAGAACUAUGCAAGCUAUAAGACAAUGGAGUAUUAUCUCUAAAUUCCUUAAUGAAAUAAACAACAAACCCUGCAACCUAGAAUUCUGUUACUGUCAAAAACGUUUUCAAAAAUGAAGGCAAAAUAAAGACUGUUUCUGAGAAACUAAAUCAAAGGUAAUUUUAUUACCUGUAGACCUGUCUUUGGGAAACAUUAAAGGAUGUUUGAGGGCAGCAGGAAAAUAAUACAAAACUUAAGUUUGGGUCUGUACAAAGGAAUGAAGUUCUGAAAAUGGUGAAUAUGUGGGUAAAUAUAAAAGAUAUUUCUCUCUUUUUAAAAUCUUUUUAAAAGGGAAUUGGCUGCUUAAAGCCAAAGUAAUGAUAACGUAUUUGGAGUUUAUUUAGAAGUAAAGUGUGAUGACGAUAACACUUAAGUGUGAAUUUUUAAAUAUAGUUGAGUAGACUGCAUCAUCUGAGUUAGAAGCCUAUUCCUUCAGGGCUCGGGGUAGCUUGAAUUUGUAGCAGGCACAUGACAGAAAUUGUAUGUAUUGUGGAUCUGCAUGUGUGCUGAGUAUUCCCUAUUUCUUUGAUCCCUUUUCCCCCAUUUUCUGCUCUGCUCCCCCCUGAGGCUGUCUUCUAGAGACUGGGGUUUCUUCAUAGGUUUGAACAGUGGGAGAUACCAGAGGUGGGAGGAGAAAAAGUUAUUUAUUACCGUUCCCUUCCUCCUGCCUGGACCAUGGUAGCUUCUGUGUUCCCGUAAGGAUACAGCUUCCUUUGGGAAGCCCCAUCUAUGGCUGUAGAUCUCUCGGUUUCAGUUGACACCAUUCCCUCUCCAUGAUCUUCAGACUUAACUACUACUGGGUGCUUCCCCAACCCACUGGUUGGGUGUCUUUAAUUGUGAACACAUAUUUGUAAAUAGUGCCUUUAUUAAUUGUUCUUGAGUUAAUAUUCUGAGUGUGCCAUUUAUUUUCUGUGCCAUCUGUUAAAUGAUGAGCAUUUAAUAAAAUUGUGAUAAUCAGUUAUCAGUACAAGUGCCGCAUAGUGCAUAGGCUGAAAUGUCUCAAGAUUCCCCACACUACAUAUCAGUAUUUUCUAUCUGUAUCUGGACAAUGCAGUAGAAAUUAUAACAAAUACAAAGUUCUUUGUGCUUUUCUGCUGCAUAUGUCAGUGGCUCUGGAGAUUGUUACCAUCUGCUACAUAUAUAAAUAGACUUGCAGUUAUUACUAAGCUCCUCUUCAGUAAUAGAAAGACUUAUGAAGUCUUUUACUACCUCUGGGUUAGCCAAACAACCUUCAAAAAGCAUUGUUAUUUAGGUUAAAUAUCUGUGGACAAGAAACAAGAUAAUCAGUUACUGAGUGAAGAAAGACGGGAAUGAUGUCCCAUACUUCCCAGCUCUCUAAAGUGUUAUGCUGUACAAUUAAAAUACCCCUGACCCAUCAUCUGCUACCAUUCGUUGUGGAUAAUUCAUGUAAUCUCUAACCUGUGGGCAAGUCUUUACCCUUCAGUAGUCAAGAUUACGUUAGAGACUUCGUCCACGAAUCCACACCACCUUUCCCAUCAGUUCUCACCGGAAAUAUGCUGCCAAAAAGAAAAUCAGCUUUUCUAAGAUCAAGCCAGAGUUGCUUCUCUUACAACCUUACGGCGCUAAUGCAUUAAGUUGAAGUCGACUGCCAAAGAGGCCCAGCAGAGGGCAGCACCCCCAUCAUUUUUUUGAAUUUCUCCCUUAGGAAUUUUGCCUUCCUUUGUCUUCUGUCCACCAGGCCUUCUCUCCAGCUGGACACAAACCUCCUUUGAAGGGAAAUAAUUGCCGUUAGGCUUCACAGUAGUGCUUUUUCCUUUCACUUGGAUUUGCAUUUUAACCUGCAUUUCGAAGAUUUUUAUACAUGUUUUCUAUUUCCGACAAUGCCAGGAGGCUUCAUUGACGUUGUAGUCUGUGUUAAUAAACUUGUGUAUCACUCUGCUCUGAUCUUUUAGGAAUUAACUUGCAAAUGAAAUGAAUAUGUUGGGACUUUGGCAUAAUUUGAAUAUAGCAUUGUGUGAGUUGUGAUUGUCUCUUCCUAAUUGUGCUGUAAUAACCUGUGUAUGAGAAUAAAAUGAUUUCCACCAUCAGGAUUCUCCCAUGCCCCCCUUUAUUUUGCCAUAGACUAAAGGGGAAAGGCCAUUCUCACUCUCCUUACCUUAGAAAAUUUUAUUUGCCUCAUGAUGACUGUCUGCCGCUUAGAAGUAGACAAUAUAAAAUCUCAUCACUAUUUCACAAGAAUAAAAUUCAAAUCAGUUAUAUCCAAAGUAACUUUUCAACUGGGGGUGGUGUCUCACACCUGUAAUCCCAGUGCUUGGGGAGGCCAAAUUGGGAGGACCGCUUGAGCCCAGGCGUUUGAGACCAGCUGGACAACAUAGCAAGACUCAUCUCUACAAAAAAAAAAUUUAAUUAGCCAUGAGAGGCUGGGUGCAGUGACGCAAGCCUGUAAUCCCAGCACUUUGGGAGGCCGAGGUGGGUGGAUCACCUGAGUUCAGGAGUUCGCGACCAGCCUGAAUAACAUGGUGAAACCCCGUCUCUACUAAAUACAAAAAAAUUAGCCGGGCAUGGUGGCACAUGCCUGUAAUCCGAGCUACUUGGGAGGCUGAGACAAGAGAAUCACUUGUACCUGGGAGGAGGAGGUUGCAGUGAGCCGAGAUCACGGCAUUGCACUCCAGUCUGGGCAACAAGAACAAAACUCCAUCUCAAAAAAAAAGUUAGCCAUGAUGGUGCAUGUCUGUAAUCCCAGCUACUUGGGAAGCUGAGGCAGAAGGGUCACUUGAGCCCAGGAGUUCAAGGCUGCAGUGAGCCAUGAUGGGGCCACUGCAUUCCAGCCUGAGUGACAGAGUGAAACCUUGCCUCUUAAAUGAAUAAAAAUAAAGUAAGCUUUCUUCAACAAGUUUUCUUCCAACGCCACACACUCCAUCACCAUAUUAAUUUAAAUUAUUUAGUAUGUAGCAGAUUUACUUUGAGACCAAAUCUGUGAAGUUGGUGAUGAUAUUUAAUAAUUCUUUAUUUCCCUUAUGGGAUCUUUGCAACUUAGAACACAAUUAUUACUCAUUGUAUCCGGGUCAUUUAACAUCUUGUCAGAAUGCUAACAUUAAAUAAACCAGGCCAGGCGCGGUGGCUCACGCCUGUAAUCCCAGCACUUUGGGAGGCCAAGGCGGGUGGAUCACGAGGUCAGGAGAUCGAGACCAUCCUGGCUAACACGGUGAAACCCCGUCUCUACUAAAAAUACAAAAAAUUAGCCAGGUGAGGUGGCCAGCGCCUGUAGUCCCAGCUACUCAGGAGGCUGAGGCAGGAGAAUGGCGUGAACCUGGGAGGUGGAGCUUGCAGUGAGCCAAGAUCACACCACUGCACUCCAGCCUGGGUGAUAGAGCGAGGCUCUGUCUCAAAAAAAUAAAUAAAUCAGGCGCUGGGCGCGGUGGCUCACACCUGUAAUCAUAACACUUUGGGAGGCUAAGGCAGGCAGAUCACAAGGUCAGGAGUUCGAGACCAGCCUGGCCAAUAUGGUGAAACCCCAUCUCUACUAAAAAUGCAAAAAUUAGCCGGGCUUGGUGGCACGUGUGUAGUCCCAGCUACUCCGGAGGCUGAGGCAGGAGAAUCGCUUGAACCCAGGAAGCCGAUGUUGCAGUGAGCUGAGAUCACACCACUGCACUCCAGCCUGGGUGACAGAGCAAGACUCCAUCACACACACACACAAAAAAACAGGGAACACCAAACUUAUUUAGUGAUACCUAAAUCUCGAAAUGUGCACAGCAAAAAGAAUGUAGCUAUCGAGGCAUUCACUGUUAAGAUGAAAAGAAAUGUAAGUGAAGGGACAUUUAUAACUUGAAGUUCUCAUUUAAGAAUUACUGGCCAGGGCCGGGCAUGGUGGCUCAUGCCUGUAAUCUCAGCACUUUGGGAGGCCAAGAUGGGUGGAUCACGAGGUCAGGAGAUUGAGACCAUCCUGGCUAACAAGGUGAAACCCCGUCUCUACUAAAAAUACAAAAAAUUAGCCGCGCGUGGUGGCGGGCGCCUGUAGUCCCAGCUACUCGGGAGGCUGAGGCAGGAGAAUGGCGUGAACCCGGGAGGCGGAGCUUGCAGUGAGCUGAGAUCGCGCCACUGCACUCACUCUGGCCUGAGCGACAAAGCGAGACUCCAUCUCAAAAAAAAAAAAAAAAAAAAAAAAGGCAUUACUGGCCAGAUGUGGUGGCUCAUGCCUGCAAUCCCAGGACUUUGGGAGGCCCAGCUGGGAGGAGAGGAGAGCUUGAGCCCAAGAGUUUGAGGCCAGCCUGGGCAACAUAGUGGCACUUUGUUCUCCACAAAAAUAAUUAAUAAAGCAAGUAAGCAUUCCUAUCACUAAAAGUACUUAAAAAAACAAAUCAAGCUUAAACUUACAAUAGGGGGUGGGAGAAGUGAAUUAACUUUUUAUUUUCAUUAGUGCGUGCUCAUGUGAAAGGAGCAGUUAGGCAAUGGAGUGUUACCACUGCAGCCAGGCAGGUCUAGUGUAGAUUCGUCCCCAAACCAUGGUAUUUGCCAGGCAGCUCUGAGGGUAUGAACAAGGCAUGUGCAUUGUGUCCUGUUGUGUGUAAUGCGUUUGUAUGAAGCAGAUUCUGUAAGAAGAUGAUGUUGGCUGAGAUGUGGGCCAGCUGUACUUCACUGCUUCAUUACAAGGGUAAGGCUGGCCAGGUGCGAUGGCUCACGCCUGUCAUCCCAGCACUUUGGGAGGCCAAGGUGGGUGGAUCACUUGAGUUCAGGAGCUCAAGAGCAGCCUGGCCAACAUGGCAAAACCCUAUCUCUACUAAACAUACAAAACAAAAAAAAUAGCCGGGUGUGGUGGAGCACCUGUAAACCCAGCUGCUCGGGAGGCUGAGGUGGGCAAAUCACAUGAACCCAGGAGUUGGAGGUUGCAGUGAGCCAAGAUGGCACCACCACUGCACUCCAGCCUGAGCAACAGAGUGAGACUCCGUCUCAAAAAAAGAGAAAACAAGGGUGGGGCUAAAAGGCUAAUAGCUAACUGAAAAUGAGCAGCUGUUUUUCAUUCUGUGAGGAGCAUCUUGUAUAAGCCGUAGUGUUUGAUCCACUCAUCAUUGCAUGGGCAGCUGUGCGAGGUCAGACCUGUUACUGACACUUCCUUCUGUGCUCUGUUUGAAAAGAAAAUCUCUGUAUGCAAAUGUUAACUGAGUAAACUGUUUCAUGAAUUCAUAUGUGUGAGUGUGAUCACUGGGAGCAAUUUGCAAAUAAACUCUGGUUUCCAUUCCAA